GCAGUCUGCAGUCUUCGUGGCGGGCCAAGCGAGCUUGGAGCCCGCGGGGGCGGAGCGGUGAGAGCGGCCGCCAAGAGAGAUCACACCCCCAGCCGACCCUGCCAGCGAGCGAGCCCGACCCCAGGCGUCCAUGGAGCGUCGCCUCCGCCCGGUCCCUGCCCCGACCCCCGCCUGCGGCGCGCUCCUGCCUUGACCAGGACUUGGGACUUUGCGAAAGGAUCGCGGGGCCCGGAGAGGUAACCGCCGCGCCUCCCGGAGAGGUAACCGCCGCGCCUCCCGGAGAGGUAACCGCCGCGCCUCCCCGUGCCGUCUGCCUCGGGCUCACCGCAGUCAAGGGCUGCGGGUGCAUGUUGGGCAGCGACCCCCGGGCUGGCACCGUCUACCUGGCGUUGGUUUUGCAGCGCUCCUGGACUGGGAGUUUGUUGGACGUUUCUGUCUGGGUUUUGAAGUGCUGGGAGUUGAGGUCACUGCUGCAGAGGUUGGAGUGACAGCCCUGGAUACCUCCAGCCAGCUGUUCCUUUCAGAUAAUGCACGGAACUUAAGCUGCAGCUGACUGGUGAAGAGGCGCCCCUCGGGCCCUCCGAUCGGGUGGUCGUUGGCGCUUUGCUCCUUUCGUGUCUUUUUUGGAGCCAAGCGUUGCAUGCUCAUGGCCACGUAGACCUUGCAGAAGCGCUGCGGCUUUUUCCCAAAUUGUGCAGGACCAGCCCGACGGGGCGUAGGGUACCGCAGUGGCCGCCAGCCCGGCGGAGGUGGGGGGCUUCAGUCCCAGAGACAGCUUCCCAGACGCUCACGGGUCCUUGCAGGGGGCUGGGGUCCUGGCGCGGGGUUCAGCUUUUCCAGUAGCAGCAGUGUAAGAGAAGUAUGCAUGUAGACGUGGGUCGCUGGCCCCUGCUCCAGCCCCUACCCCACGGUUAGACUGUCUUUGUCAGCUGGAGUCGUCCCACAUCCUGCCACCUGGCCUCUCAGAAAAGCAGUGGCAUUAAGUGUUGGAGAGCACAAUGGCUGAACAAGUCCUUCCUCAGGCUUUGUAUUUGAGCAAUAUGCGGAAAGCUGUGAAGAUACGGGAGAGAACUCCAGAAGACAUUUUUAAACCUACUAAUGGGAUCAUUCAUCAUUUUAAAACCAUGCACCGAUACACACUGGAAAUGUUCAGAACUUGCCAGUUUUGUCCUCAGUUUCGGGAGAUCAUCCACAAAGCCCUCAUCGACAGAAACAUCCAGGCCACCCUGGAAAGCCAGAAGAAACUCAACUGGUGUCGAGAAGUCCGGAAGCUUGUGGCGCUGAAAACGAACGGUGACGGCAAUUGCCUCAUGCAUGCCACUUCUCAGUACAUGUGGGGCGUUCAGGACACAGACUUGGUACUGAGGAAGGCGCUGUUCAGCACGCUCAAGGAAACAGACACACGCAACUUUAAAUUCCGCUGGCAACUGGAGUCUCUCAAAUCUCAGGAAUUUGUUGAAACGGGGCUUUGCUAUGAUACUCGGAACUGGAAUGAUGAAUGGGACAAUCUUAUCAAAAUGGCUUCCACAGACACACCCAUGGCCCGAAGUGGACUUCAGUACAACUCACUGGAAGAAAUACACAUAUUUGUCCUUUGCAACAUCCUCAGAAGGCCAAUCAUUGUCAUUUCAGACAAAAUGCUAAGAAGUUUGGAAUCAGGUUCCAAUUUCGCCCCUUUGAAAGUGGGUGGAAUUUACUUGCCUCUCCACUGGCCUGCCCAGGAAUGCUACAGAUACCCCAUUGUUCUCGGCUAUGACAGCCAUCAUUUUGUACCCUUGGUGACCCUGAAGGACAGUGGGCCUGAAAUCCGAGCUGUUCCACUUGUUAACAGAGACCGGGGAAGAUUUGAAGACUUAAAAGUUCACUUUUUGACAGAUCCUGAAAAUGAGAUGAAGGAGAAGCUCUUAAAAGAGUACUUAAUGGUGAUAGAAAUCCCCGUCCAAGGCUGGGACCAUGGCACAACUCAUCUCAUCAAUGCCGCAAAGUUGGAUGAAGCUAACUUACCAAAAGAAAUCAAUCUGGUAGAUGAUUACUUUGAACUUGUUCAGCAUGAGUACAAGAAAUGGCAGGAAAACAGCGAGCAGGGGAGGAGAGAGGGGCACGCCCAGAAUCCCAUGGAACCUUCCGUGCCCCAGCUUUCUCUCAUGGAUGUAAAAUGUGAAACGCCCAACUGCCCCUUCUUCAUGUCUGUGAACACCCAGCCUUUAUGCCAUGAGUGCUCAGAGAGGCGGCAAAAGAAUCAAAACAAACUCCCAAAGCUGAACUCCAAGCCGGGCCCUGAGGGGCUCCCUGGCAUGGCGCUCGGGGCCUCUCGGGGAGAAGCCUAUGAGCCCUUGGCGUGGAACCCUGAGGAGUCCACUGGGGGGCCUCAUUCGGCCCCACCGACAGCACCCAGCCCUUUUCUGUUCAGUGAGACCACUGCCAUGAAGUGCAGGAGCCCCGGCUGCCCCUUCACACUGAAUGUGCAGCACAACGGAUUUUGUGAACGUUGCCACAACGCCCGGCAACUUCACGCCAGCCACGCCCCAGACCACACAAGGCACUUGGAUCCCGGGAAGUGCCAAGCCUGCCUCCAGGAUGUUACCAGGACAUUUAAUGGGAUCUGCAGUACUUGCUUCAAAAGGACUACAGCAGAGGCCUCCUCCAGCCUCAGCACCAGCCUCCCUCCUUCCUGUCACCAGCGUUCCAAGUCAGAUCCCUCGCGGCUCGUCCGGAGCCCCUCCCCGCAUUCUUGCCACAGAGCUGGAAACGACGCCCCUGCUGGCUGCCUGUCUCAAGCUGCACGGACUCCUGGGGACAGGACGGGGACGAGCAAGUGCAGAAAAGCCGGCUGCGUGUAUUUUGGGACUCCAGAAAACAAGGGCUUUUGCACACUGUGUUUCAUCGAGUACAGAGAAAACAAACAUUUUGCUGCUGCCUCAGGGAAAGUCAGUCCCACAGCGUCCAGGUUCCAGAACACCAUUCCGUGCCUGGGGAGGGAAUGCGGCACCCUUGGAAGCACCAUGUUUGAAGGAUACUGCCAGAAGUGUUUCAUUGAAGCUCAGAAUCAGAGAUUUCAUGAGGCCAAAAGGACAGAAGAGCAACUGAGAUCGAGCCAGCGCAGAGAUGUGCCUCGAACCACACAAAGCACCUCAAGGCCCAAGUGCGCCCGGGCCUCCUGCAAGAACAUCCUGGCCUGCCGCAGCGAGGAGCUCUGCAUGGAGUGUCAGCAUCCCAACCAGAGGAUGGGCCCUGGGGCCCACCGGGGUGAGCCUGCCCCCGAAGACCCCCCCAAGCAGCGUUGCCGGGCCCCCGCCUGUGAUCAUUUUGGCAAUGCCAAGUGCAACGGCUACUGCAACGAAUGCUUUCAGUUCAAGCAGAUGUAUGGCUAACCGGAAACAGGUGGGUCACCUCCUGCAAGAAGUGGGGCCUCGAGCUGUCAGUCAUCAUGGUGCUAUCCUCUGAACCCCUCAGCUGCCACUGCAACAGUGGGCUUAAGGGUGUCUGAGCAGGAGAGGAAAGAUAAGCUCUUCGUGGUGCCCACGAUGCUCAGGUUUGGUAACCCGGGAGUGUUCCCAGGUGGCCUUAGAAAGCAAAGCUUGUAACUGGCAAGGGAUGAUGUCAGAUUCAGCCCAAGGUUCCUCCUCUCCUACCAAGCAGGAGGCCAGGAACUUCUUUGGACUUGGAAGGUGUGCGGGGACUGGCCGAGGCCCCUGCACCCUGCGCAUCAGGACUGCUUCAUCGUCUUGGCUGAGAAAGGGAAAAGACACACAAGUCGCGUGGGUUGGAGAAGCCAGAGCCAUUCCACCUCCCCUCCCCCAGCAUCUCUCAGAGAUGUGAAGCCAGAUCCUCAUGGCAGCGAGGCCCUCUGCAAGAAGCUCAAGGAAGCUCAGGGAAAAUGGACGUAUUCAGAGAGUGUUUGUAGUUCAUGGUUUUUCCCUACCUGCCCGGUUCCUUUCCUGAGGACCCGGCAGAAAUGCAGAACCAUCCAUGGACUGUGAUUCUGAGGCUGCUGAGACUGAACAUGUUCACAUUGACAGAAAAACAAGCUGCUCUUUAUAAUAUGCACCUUUUAAAAAAUUAGAAUAUUUUACUGGGAAGACGUGUAACUCUUUGGGUUAUUACUGUCUUUACUUCUAAAGAAGUUAGCUUGAACUGAGGAGUAAAAGUGUGUACAUAUAUAAUAUACCCUUACAUUAUGUAUGAGGGAUUUUUUUAAAUUAUAUUGAAAUGCUGCCCUAGAAGUACAAUAGGAAGGCUAAAUAAUAAUAACCUGUUUUCUGGUUGUUGUUGGGGCAUGAGCUUGUGUAUACACUGCUUGCAUAAACUCAACCAGCUGCCUUUUUAAAGGGAGCUCUAGUCCUUUUUGUGUAAUUCACUUUAUUUAUUUUAUUACAAACUUCAAGAUUAUUUAAGUGAAGAUAUUUCUUCAGCUCUGGGGAAAAUGCCACAGUGUUCUCCUGAGAGAACAUCCUUGCUUUGAGUCAGGCUGUGGGCAAGUUCCUGACCACAGGGAGUAAAUUGGCCUCUUUGAUACACUUUUGCUUGCCUCCCCAGGAAAGAAGGAAUUGCAUCCAAGGUAUACAUACAUAUUCAUCGAUGUUUCGUGCUUCUCCUUAUGAAACUCCAGCUAUGUAAUAAAAAACUAUACUCUGUGUUCUGUUAAUGCCUCUGAGUGUCCUACCUCCUUGGAGAUGAGAUAGGGAAGGAGCAGGGAUGAGACUGGCAAUGGUCACAGGGAAAGAUGUGGCCUUUUGUGAUGGUUUUAUUUUCUGUUAACACUGUGUCCUGGGGGGGCUGGGAAGUCCCCUGCAUCCCAUGGUACCCUGGUAUUGGGACAGCAAAAGCCAGUAACCAUGAGUAUGAGGAAAUCUCUUUCUGUUGCUGGCUUACAGUUUCUCUGUGUGCUUUGUGGUUGCUGUCAUAUUUGCUCUAGAAGAAAAAAAAAAAAGGAGGGGAAAUGCAUUUUCCCCAGAGAUAAAGGCUGCCAUUUUGGGGGUCUGUACUUAUGGCCUGAAAAUAUUUGUGAUCCAUAACUCUACACAGCCUUUACUCAUACUAUUAGGCACACUUUCCCCUUAGAGCCCCCUAAGUUUUUCCCAGACGAAUCUUUAUAAUUUCUUUCCAAAGAUACCAAAUAAACUUCAGUGUUUUCAUCUAAUUCUCUUAAAGUUGAUAUCUUAAUAUUUUGUGUUGAUCAUUAUUUCCAUUCUUAAUGUGAAAAAAAGUAAUUAUUUAUACUUAUUAUAAAAAGUAUUUGAAAUUUGCACAUUUAAUUGUCCCUAAUAGAAAGCCACCUAUUCUUUGUUGGAUUUCUUCAAGUUUUUCUAAAUAAAUGUAACUUUUCACAAGAGUCAACAUUAAAAAAUAAAUUAUUUAAGAACA